AGAGGGGCCAAGUUCCGGCGUCCGCGCGGAGGGCAACUUGGGUUCGCGCUCCGCUGGAGACCACCGCGCCCGGCCCAUCGGAGGCGAUCCGUUCCCGGGUCUCCCAAACUAGUUCCCGAAGCCAGACCCGCGGCGCUCGCAGUGCCGAAUUUUGGACCAGCUUUUUCGUUUCAUUUCCUCACUUUGCGUUGUAGUCGUCUCAAAGGGAAAUGCUUUGUGGUCUACAGCCACACCACCCCAAAUGUGCCUGAUCUUGUCUGAUCUUGGAAGCUAAGCAUUGUUGGGCCUAGUUAGGACCUGGAUAGGAGAAAUCCCUUAUGGCUAACUAUAUGUCAGAAAGCAUCAGCUUUUCUCGAUGGACCCAUUCAUCUAAUGAAAUAUGCCUGUACUAUUUUAAAAAGCUUUGUAUUUCGUCAUAGAAAAGUUCAUCCCCCCAGAAUGAAAAUGAGGACAUUUGAGAAGGUGAUUUAAGGUGUGGACAUUUGAGAAGGUGUCCUAUCAAAUUAGUAAACCAAAGGAAAAGUACUGAAUAGAUUAAUCCAAAACACUUACUGUUUUUUAAACGAAGAGGAUUUCACCUUGACAGAAAAACAACUUUUAUUCAAUAUGUAUUUCCUGAAAUUAAAGAGACAAGUACAGACUGAAAGGAAAAUAGAUUCGUAAAUAAGCUACGUCAACUCUAUCCUGCUGAGGAUAGCUCAGUGAUGUUAAAUCCUUUACAAAUCCCUGGUUGUCUUCCUACAGACAAGACUGCUUUUUGAUGGGACUGAUAUUAAGAGAAAUAGGACCUUUGGGGCAUUCAACUCCUUGAUAAAACUUAAAAGUAUCGGCAUGAGUGGCUUAACAGAGGAAAUAAAGAAGUUUUCAACUAAAUCCAAAAGUGCGGUCAUUUUCUUUACUGCUGUUAUUUUAAAAACCUCUUCAUAACCAUUGAAAAAGAAUCGACAACUAUUUUAAAAGAUUAAAGAAAGGCAGAUGUCUGCAAAUAAUUCCCCUCCAUCAGCCCAGAAGUCUGUAUUACCCACAGCUAUUCCUGCUGUGCUUCCAGCUGCUUCUCCGUGUUCAAGUCCUAAGACGGGACUCUCUGCCCGACUCUCUAAUGGAAGCUUCAGUGCACCAUCACUCACCAACUCCAGAGGCUCAGUGCAUACAGUUUCAUUUCUACUGCAAAUUGGCCUCACACGGGAGAGUGUUACCAUUGAAGCCCAGGAACUGUCUUUAUCUGCUGUCAAGGAUCUUGUGUGCUCCAUAGUUUAUCAAAAGUUUCCAGAGUGUGGAUUCUUUGGCAUGUAUGACAAAAUUCUUCUCUUUCGCCAUGACAUGAACUCAGAAAACAUUUUGCAGCUGAUUACCUCAGCAGAUGAAAUACAUGAAGGAGACCUAGUGGAAGUGGUUCUUUCAGCUUUAGCCACAGUAGAAGACUUCCAGAUUCGUCCACAUACUCUCUAUGUACAUUCUUACAAAGCUCCUACUUUCUGUGAUUACUGUGGUGAGAUGCUCUGGGGAUUGGUACGUCAAGGACUGAAAUGUGAAGGCUGUGGAUUAAAUUACCAUAAACGAUGUGCCUUCAAGAUUCCAAAUAACUGUAGUGGAGUAAGAAAGAGACGUCUGUCAAAUGUAUCUUUACCAGGACCCGGCCUCUCAGUUCCAAGACCCCUACAGCCUGAAUAUGUAGCCCUUCCCAGUGAAGAGUCACAUGUCCACCAGGAACCAAGUAAGAGAAUUCCUUCUUGGAGUGGUCGCCCAAUCUGGAUGGAAAAGAUGGUAAUGUGCAGAGUGAAAGUUCCACACACAUUUGCUGUUCACUCUUACACCCGUCCCACGAUAUGUCAGUACUGCAAGCGGUUACUGAAAGGCCUCUUUCGCCAAGGAAUGCAGUGUAAAGAUUGCAAAUUCAACUGCCAUAAACGCUGUGCAUCAAAAGUACCAAGAGACUGCCUUGGAGAGGUUACUUUCAAUGGAGAACCUUCCAGUCUGGGAACAGAUACAGAUAUACCAAUGGAUAUUGACAAUAAUGACAUAAAUAGUGAUAGUAGUCGGGGUUUGGAUGACACAGAAGAGCCAUCACCCCCAGAAGAUAAGAUGUUCUUCUUGGAUCCAUCUGAUCUCGAUGUGGAAAGAGAUGAAGAAGCCGUUAAAACAAUCAGUCCAUCAACAAGCAAUAAUAUUCCGCUAAUGAGGGUUGUACAAUCCAUCAAGCACACAAAGAGGAAGAGCAGCACAAUGGUGAAGGAAGGGUGGAUGGUCCAUUACACCAGCAGGGAUAACCUGAGAAAGAGGCAUUAUUGGAGACUUGACAGCAAAUGUCUAACAUUAUUUCAGAAUGAAUCUGGAUCAAAGUAUUAUAAGGAAAUUCCACUUUCAGAAAUUCUCCGCAUAUCUUCACCACGAGAUUUCACAAACAUUUCACAAGGCAGCAAUCCACACUGUUUUGAAAUCAUUACUGAUACUAUGGUAUACUUCGUUGGUGAGAACAAUGGGGACAGCUCUCAUAAUCCUGUUCUUGCUGCCACUGGAGUUGGACUUGAUGUAGCACAGAGCUGGGAAAAAGCAAUUCGCCAAGCCCUCAUGCCUGUUACUCCUCAAGCAAGUGUUUGCACUUCUCCAGGGCAAGGGAAAGAUCACAAAGAUUUGUCUACAAGUAUCUCUGUAUCUAAUUGUCAGAUUCAGGAGAAUGUGGAUAUCAGUACUGUUUACCAGAUCUUUGCAGAUGAGGUGCUUGGUUCAGGCCAGUUUGGCAUCGUUUAUGGAGGAAAACAUAGAAAGACUGGGAGGGAUGUGGCUAUUAAAGUAAUUGAUAAGAUGAGAUUCCCCACAAAACAAGAAAGUCAACUCCGUAAUGAAGUGGCUAUUUUACAGAAUUUGCACCAUCCUGGGAUUGUAAACCUGGAAUGUAUGUUUGAAACCCCAGAACGAGUCUUUGUAGUAAUGGAAAAGCUGCAUGGAGAUAUGUUGGAAAUGAUUCUAUCCAGUGAGAAAAGUCGGCUUCCAGAACGAAUUACUAAAUUCAUGGUCACACAGAUACUUGUUGCUUUGAGGAAUCUGCAUUUUAAGAAUAUUGUGCACUGUGAUUUAAAGCCAGAAAAUGUGCUGCUUGCAUCAGCAGAGCCAUUUCCUCAGGUGAAGCUGUGUGACUUUGGAUUUGCACGCAUCAUUGGUGAAAAGUCAUUCAGGAGAUCUGUGGUAGGAACUCCAGCAUACUUAGCCCCUGAAGUUCUCCGGAGCAAAGGUUACAACCGUUCCCUAGAUAUGUGGUCAGUGGGAGUUAUCAUCUAUGUGAGCCUCAGUGGCACAUUUCCUUUUAAUGAGGAUGAAGAUAUAAAUGACCAAAUCCAAAAUGCUGCAUUUAUGUACCCACCAAAUCCAUGGAGAGAAAUUUCUGGUGAAGCAAUUGAUCUGAUAAACAAUCUGCUUCAAGUGAAGAUGAGAAAACGUUACAGUGUUGACAAAUCUCUUAGUCAUCCCUGGCUACAGGACUAUCAGACUUGGCUUGACCUUAGAGAAUUUGAAACUCGCAUUGGAGAACGUUACAUUACACAUGAAAGUGAUGAUGCUCGCUGGGAAAUACAUGCAUACACACAUAACCUUGUAUACCCAAAGCACUUCAUUAUGGCUCCUAAUCCAGAUGAUAUGGAAGAAGAUCCUUAAUCACUGAGCUAACCUAAAUAAGGAAGGAUUUCAUUUUAUGGACUGAUAUUUUGCUGUGUAACUUGUUCUUUGUAGAUUGUCAUCUGCAGUGCUGCAAAGAUAUGAAGAAAUAUGAUAACGAAUAAGUGACACCAGUACUGUAGUUCAUAAUGAGUAGGUACAGGCGGGAAACUGAAUAAUAAGAAGUCAUAAUGGAAUCAAGGUGAAGCUUUUUAUAAACUUUUUUAGCCUAAGCAAUAACUGGUUUUGUAUUUUUUCUUAAUCCUUCACUUUAAUACAAUAGGCUCACUUAAUUUGUCUUCCCAUUUCUCUUUAUAUAUAUAUAUAUAAAUAUAAAUAUAUGUUUGUUUGUUUUUUUAAUGAAAAACAAGUCAAGCUAGCAUCCAGUUACUAUAUAGCUUGGCUAAAUUAUACAAGACUUACAAGAUUGAUUACUCGACAGGCUUGUAUUUAAGAGGUAACUGUGAGGUUACCAUUAUGUGAUGUUACUAUAAGGACUUUUAACAUUGGUUUAACAAACCAUAGAGGCAUUGAAGGGUUUUUCUUAGAUGCCUAGAAAAAGCGCACUGGGCUGUUUUACCUUUCUUUUUUAGGUCAAUCAAGACUCCAAAAUAGUGAUUCCUAACCUUUUUGGAGUUGCUCUGCUACUCUGAAUAUGUUCUAUACAGCAUAAGGAUUGUCACCUUCUGUGUGUUGCAACAGCUUCUAAGAUAAUUAGGGACAAAUGAUGUUACAAAAGGAAGAGUACUGCUGGUCUAAGUGCUGAGUUGUAUGUCUUUGCAUAGCUCCACUCUGCUGCUAAAUAUGCAUGUUCUGACUGACACCAUCUUGAUGCCAGUACUGGAUUCCAGCAUUCAGCAGGUGCAGAUCUCGGCUUUACACAAUUUAUCUUUACCUAGGGUUCAGUCAGUAAUUUCUGCUUUUUAGCAGGGCCAGUGCAGGGUCAGUUAAUGCUACAGUUACUGUAUAGCAAACAGUAUCCUUUUUUCUCCUUCCCCUAGCCUAUUGGGCUUUGCAGAUAUCUGGAGUGUUUUAAAGUCAAUUAUUUUAAGCAGUUUGAGGGGAUGUGUAGGAGUGGAGCAUGAAACAGUUUAUAAGGCUGGGGCUGUAUUAUCAGCACAGCAAAUUAAAGAAUGAAAGAAGUACUUCUUUUUACAUUUCAGCUCCAGCAGCCAGCUAUUUAAAAAAUAUUUUUAAAUAUCUUCCCCAAAGUUUAAGAUGUGGGACCAUCUACUUGUAAGAAACAGUGGCUUAUUUCUUCAUUUCUCAGUAAUCAUUGUAAACCUUUUUUUUUUUCUUCUCCACUCUAACAAAAGUAAAAGAACAAAACUUUUGCUGAGGUCUUGGACUCCACUACUUGUUAGUUAUGUUGGCCUGGACAGAUGGCAGGUCUGUCGGCAGUUCCUCAGUCUGUAAAAUGAAGAUUAUCAUUCUUGCCUCUCCCUUUGUCACAGUGUUGUCGUGAAGAUCAGAUAUGUAUGAAUGCAGUCAAAUAAACUAAAAACUAGGAAAGUGUUAACUAUCGUUGCCCACCGAAUUUGAGGUAGCAAAAAAAAAAAAGAAUGUUCUGGUACAUGAACAGACUGAGAAGGCCUUUCGACAUCCCUGAAGCUAGUCUCCUGUCUAGACUAAAAAUAUCCUUGAAAGAAUAGUAGCAAACAGUAUGCAGUACUCCUGUGUUCUAAGUUCUUUUAUGUUUUAGUUUACCCUCACAGCAGCCAUAGUGUUAAGUCAUUAUGAGCUUCAUCUUAAAGAUAAGAAAACUGAGGCAAGGGGAGAUUAACUUACUGCCAAAUUUCAAACAGUUAGUAGUAUUUGAGACCAGUAGUAUGGCUCUAAUCUUACCCUUAGCCCUCCCAACCAUUAUGCUGUACUAUCUACCCAUAAAUACCUCCAGGAAACAUUCCCCUCUUGGUAAUUUGUCCUUCUAUAGAAGCUUCAAAGAUUAAAUCAAAUUAAUUUUCAAAAAAAAUUUUUUUUUAGAAAUGUUAUUUUCCCUGUGAUAGAGGAUGACUUCCCAGUUUCACCAAAGUCUGUUUAUAUCAACACACACAAAAUGGAAUAAUUCUGAGUCACUAGGCAAUCAAUCUACUGUGGUUUUACUAUGUAAGGUGAAAAUUAACUGGAACGAUGUUUGUUUGCUAUACUUACAUAGUCAAACUUUACAAGCCAUGAAAUUAAUUGCACUCUUUGUAUUUGUUGUUAAAUGCCUAAGAAGUUUUCUAAAAAUUUUGUAAAGGCACUGUCAGAGAAUCUGGAGUUGAAUGAUUAUUCCAGAUACUGUAUAACCUGCAUAACUUUUUGUCUUUAAGUCGUGUUUGUAAAAGAAGUAAUUGCUAGAAACAUUUGAUAAUGUACAAAGUAGUCUAUAAUGACUGUUCAGUACAUUUUUAAUAUUUUUUUGGUUAUAUCCAACUUUUUGUAAAUAUACUGGAAGCUUGAUAAUAAAAUGUAUUUCCUAUCACCAUACUUUUCCAUGUGAAAACCUGAGCCUAUUUCUAGUAUAAGUAUCCAAAGAAAAGUUUGACCUGGUUGUGUUAUUUUACCAGACCUUGGUAAAAGAACUAUUUUGGAAACAGUAUUUGUAAAUGGAACUAAUGCUAUAUUUAAAAACACUGAUUUUUUUUUAACCUGCCAAAAAUAAAAAAAAGCUCAUUUUAUAAUUUUCUACUAAA